CUUUCUUGGGCUCUAAGGACCCAGGAGUCUGGGUGCACAGCCUCCUUCUCUCUGAGAUUCAAGAGUCUGAUCAGCAGCCUCUUCCUCCUCCAGGACCCAGAAGCCCUGAGCUUAUCCCCAUGGAGCUCUGCCGGUCCCUGGCCCUGCUGGGGGGCUCCCUGGGCCUGAUGUUCUGCCUGAUUGCUUUGAGCACCGAUUUCUGGUUUGAGGCUGUGGGUCCCACCCACUCAGCUCACUCGGGCCUCUGGCCAACAGGGCAUGGGGACAUCAUAUCAGGCUACAUCCACGUGACGCAGACCUUCAGCAUUAUGGCUGUUCUGUGGGCCCUGGUGUCCGUGAGCUUCCUGGUCCUGUCCUGCUUCCCCUCACUGUUCCCCCCAGGCCACGGCCCGCUUGUCUCAACCACCGCAGCCUUUGCUGCAGCCAUCUCCAUGGUGGUGGCCAUGGCGGUGUACACCAGCGAGCGGUGGGACCAGCCUCCACACCCCCAGAUCCAGACCUUCUUCUCCUGGUCCUUCUACCUGGGCUGGGUCUCAGCUAUCCUCUUGCUCUGUACAGGUGCCCUGAGCCUGGGUGCUCACUGUGGCGGUCCCCGUCCUGGCUAUGAAACCUUGUGAGCAGAAGGCAAGAGCGGCAAGAUGAGUUUUGAGCGUUGUAUUCCAAAGGCCUCAUCUGGAGCCUCGGGAAAGUCUGGUCCCACAUCUGCCCGCCCUUCCAGCCCUUCCCCAGCCCCUCCUCUUGUUUCUUCAUUCAUUCAACAAAAUUUGGCUGGAA